GCAGUUGAGCGCACGCUCAGAGCAGACCGCUAGCAGGAGGCAGGAUGUGAUAGUCUAAGACCCUGGAAGCUGACGGCCAGAGGGAGGGAAGGGUGGUCACAGAGGAGAGGCAAAGCAACGGGAGGUGGAGGAUCCUGGAGGUGUCUGCAAGGAGAAUACACAGCAGCGAGGGGCUGCAGAAGCGGACCCAGCGACUUCUGCGCUGACGCGGGGCGGGCGGGAGAGAGGAAGAGAGGGGAGCGCGGUGGCGCUGCGAGCUGGCCCCGCCGGGGAAGGGGCUGCCAUGUCCCGUGAGCGGCCCCCGGGCACCGACAUUCCCCGCAACCUGAGCUUCAUCGCCGCGCUAACGGAGCGCGCCUACUACCGUAGCCAGCGGCCCAGCCUCGAGGAGGAGCCGGAGGAGGAGCCAGGCGAGGGCGGGACGCGGUUCGGGGCCCGAUCCCGCGCUCACGCACCGAGUCGGGGCCGCCGGGCCCGAUCUGCACCAGCCGGAGGCGGCGGGGCCCGGGCGCCCCGCAGCCGUAGCCCAGACACCCGCAAGAGAGUGCGUUUCGCCGACGCACUGGGGUUGGAGCUGGCUGUCGUGCGCCGCUUCCGUCCCGGUGAGCUGCCCCGGGUGCCCCGCCACGUGCAGAUCCAAUUGCAGAGGGACGCCCUCCGCCACUUCGCGCCCUGCCAGCCCCGCGCCCGCGGCCUCCAGGAGGCGCGCGCCGCCCUGGAGCCGGCCAGCGAGCCCGGCUUCGCCGCCCGCUUGCUGACGCAGCGCAUCUGCCUGGAACGCGCCGAGGCGGGCCCGCUGGGCGUGGCCGGGAGCGCGCGCGUGGUGGACCUGGCCUACGAGAAGCGCGUGAGCGUGCGCUGGAGCGCCGACGGCUGGCGGAGCCAACGCGAGGCGCCAGCCGCCUACGCCGGUCCGGCCCCGCCCCCGCCGCGCGCCGACCGCUUCGCCUUCCGCCUGCCCGCGCCGCCGAUUGGGGGCGCCCUGCUCUUCGCCUUGCGCUACCGUGUGACAGGUCACGAGUUCUGGGACAACAACGGCGGCCGUGACUAUGCUCUACGUGGGCCCGAGCACCCGGGCAGUGGCGGAGCUCCGGAGCCGCAGGGCUGGAUCCACUUUAUCUGAGACGAGGCGCCUGCGGCCGACGGCGGAAAACACCAAAGGCACCCGGGGGCGGGGCGACCCGAUGUGGCGGGGAGGAGUAGGAGAGACCAGGAUUGGCGGGAGCGGUCCAAGGGAGUCAAGCCGGGGAGGGCGAAAAGGGAACCUGGCCACUGCUCCUUGGUCCUUGGCAUUAUGACGGGAUUCCCUUGUCACCUCUGACAGUUCCUGGCUGCGGUGUCCGCGGACUGGCUGGGGAGUGAUGACAGAAGGGAUGGAAACCCUAUUUUCUUUUCUCCAAGACCAUGGUUGGUCUGCUUCCCUCACUCGGGCUCCUUGACAGUCUUCUAGAAGAGAGAAGGAGGAAAAGAAGCAGUUCCUGAUGUUACAAAUGAACAAGGAUCUCCCAGCCUUAGUCUUUGAGAAAAGAUGGCUGAAAGAGAGGAACUCUCCAAGUCAUUCCGCAAACAAAUGCCCAUUUAAACAUCAUCCUUGUCUUGUGAAGAAAACAGGAAGAAUGUCAUGUACCAUGUGGAUCACCUUCAGUUCAAAGUUGCAGCAAAGUGAAGAAAGAAACUACUGGAAGCCACCCAGCAAUGCACUGUUUAGUCAUCAAUUAGGAGCCCAUGGGAGGAUAAUAGGGAGACUGGGUGGAGGCUCAGUGUGUAAUAAUCUCUUGUCUAAUGUAUGUGUGUCACUGCCAUGUUGUAUGAACAAUAGUGAGGGCUCACAUUUACUUAACACUUGUGUGCGCAAAUCUGGGUUUUUCUUCCUUUCCAGAACUAUGACUCGAUCAUAAAAUCUGUUUUGUUUGCAUGCAUGCCCAAAACAACCCUGUAAGUAGAACAUUGUCAUUAUCUCUGUUUUAGAGAUGAGGAAACAGGCUCAGAGAAGCUCAGAAAUUUGUUCAAGAUCGCACAGCUAGUAAAUGGCAGAAGUAGGAUUGUGAACCCAGGGAAUCUCCAGAGCCUCUGUGUAACCAUGAUGUUAUAUUUUUUUUCCUCUUUAAAAACAAAAUUUAAAACCUUGCUAUAAUCUCUUAUUAGGAAAUGAUCAUAGUUUCUGACUGUGCUCUGCCUUCCCAUCCUGCCAAUCUCCUGGACUGGCUUGGAGAAGACAGGGGGCCCCCGAGCUUCAUCUGUGACUCGAAGGAGUUUGCUGCUGUCUCCUGUGUCAGUGUCCCAUCUAUGCAGGAUCAGCACAGGACCCCCCUCACCUUCCCACUUACACUCUAGCCUUUCCAUACAUUGGAAUUCUCUCCUGGCCCUAGCCAGCGCUCCACACCUGUUGGUGUGCCACCUCCCUCCCUCUUCCCCCACUGGCCUUGAACAGGCAAACCCCCUAAUGUCGCCACUAGGUUGGGUCCGUGACUAGGACACCUGCUAGAGGGUCUGUGCUUGGGCCUUUUCUAGGAAUCCCGAUGUUACUGGGUAAGUGCCAACUCUGUGGGCAGAAUGCUAAUGAUAAUCCUGUUCCCUGACCUCUUUCUCAGAAGUACCCUGGCUCACUCUCCCCAAUCUCAGCUUUAUAGAACAACAUUUUGGUCUUGAUUAUUCCCAUAUCAAGCUGCCCCAGGGCUUCGGUAAGCUGUUAGUUGCCCCACUGCCUCAAGGCUGGGUCUGGCUGAGCUACUUCUUAGGCACACAAAUAGUGGGUGUCUCCUUGGAACCUGACACAAAACUAUCAGUGCUACCAAGCCUUGUAAAAUAGGGAGGAAACUAAUAUUUCUUGAGUGGCUUCUGAGUGCCUGGUGCUUUCGCGGCUCUCUGGAGAGAUUCCUUGCCCUGAUGGCUUUGGUGUGUACUCCUCUCCCAGGACUUCAGCACUGAGAUUUUCCCAACCCCCUGGCUUUUCCUCACCUUGGGUUGAGUUGAUCCGGCACUACCACAAACCCCACCAUCUGCAAACCAACCAAGAUUAGGCAGUAUGCCCUUUCCGUCUUGCACUGCUCUUCCAAAACUUCCAUCUGUAUUUCUCACACCCUCAGUAAGCAAAGCUGAGUGUGCAUGGACAGAGCUGCAUCCACUGCUUUCUCCCAGCGGGUGCAGUCUAAUCUGACACGGGGAACACUAGGAGUUUAGCGGAAUCUUCAGCCACCCUAUUAAUGUGUUACGCAUUAGGCAUUGUAGUGGAAACUCCUCUGAUGGCUCAUGACUAUAUGAACAGGAGCAAUUUGGAAUAUAACAUGUCAGCUGUGGACUGGGAAGUGCCGUGAGAGAAAACACUACCUGGGUCAUAGGCUUGGGUCCCUGAGGCAACCCAGCAGGGACACUGUUGCCCAUUCCUCUCAUCCAGACUGCAGGUGUCUUCCUACACCUCCCUGUCCCAUAGCCUCCGUCCUGUUUUUUGUUUGUUUGUUUUUCUUUGUGAAUGUAGAAAAACAUUUCAUCAUGAGCCCUAGCUCCUCAGUUUUCCACCUAACACCCACAUUCCCUUGUUUCUAACUGCCGUGUUUUUCUGGAGCCUGCUGGGAUCUUUGCAGUUUGCAGGUCAUAGAAUCAGACAUGAAAAGGCUUCUCUUCCGACGUCAUUGGUUCCUGGCUCCUUUACAGAUGAGAACACAGGUCCAGAGGUGAGAAAUGACUCUAGCAGGGUCAUAGAAUUUGUUAGUGCAGCUCAAGAUGGGACUUAAACUCAGGCCUCCUGAUCACCCAUUCCCAGGCUAGGAAACAGGUCUCUGCUCGGUGUGGUGGUUCAUACCUGUAAUCGCAACACUUUGGGAGGCUGAGGCAGGAGCAUUGCUUGAGCCCAGGAGUUCGAGACCAGUCUGAGCAACAUAGUGGGACCCUGUCUCUACAAAAACUUUUAAAAUUAGCUGGGCAUGGUGGCACACAUCUGUAUUCCCAGCUACUCAGGAAGCUGAGACAGGAGGAUCGCUUGAGCCCAGGAGUUGGAGGUUACUGAGCUAUGAUCGCACCACUGCACUCCAGCUUGGUGACAGUGAGACCCUCAAAAAAAAAAAGAAAAGAAAGAGGUCUCUACACAAGCCCGUGAUUCUUCAUGGCAAGGGAUAACAUCAGAAAUGUUUCAUUUUCUGCUAUUAGUUUCCAUUCCUUUCCCCAUCCAGGCAUAAAGAGAAACAAAAGACAAUGAUGGUAUUCUCUGUGUCCUCAGCUUUGGCACUUUUGUUGAUGUUGCUAAGGAGCAGUGACCUUGCUAAAAAGACUGAAUAAUCCACCCACUGAAUAGCUAACCUGGGGAGGAAAUGAAAAUUUCCUUUGUGGAUCUCCCCAAAUCCAUUGUUGUCACCAGGCCCUCCCAGAACCUCCUCAGUUCCUUCACAGUGCAACCCUGUGUACUUGGCCCGCAACCCAAUAGUAUUGUGCCUCACUUCACCUUCCAUGGGCAACUGCCCUCCCUUCUGGACAUAAAACCUCAUAUUUUAAAUAAAGUUGAAAUAUGAAAAGAAAGUAUGUCAUAAGAUAUUCAGAAGUAUUGUGUGUUUUGGGCUAAGGGCAGCAAGAGACUCAGAGGCAAGAUUCCCUCCUUGACUCAAUUUCUUGGUCACCUUGUUUUUUGUGUGUGUGUGUCCAGAAAAAUUUAAUAAGUUUGCUUAAAUUAUUAUAAAGUUGAACCACUGAAAUGUUCACUGAAACAUUUUGACUUGCAUUAAUGCUUUACUUCCCCACCUACAUUUACAUUAAAAAUUCACACACAAAUGAAAAUUGAAAACUGA